ACAGAUAUUUAUUCUUUCUACAUAAGUGUAGGACUUUUUCCCUUAUUUUUCUAGAAAAUGUUUAUAUUUCUAAAGUUUGCUUUUGAAUUCUUUUUUUAAAAAGCUAUUUUAAUUGUUUCACAGUGUGAAGCAUUAGAAUCACAGAACUGUAAGGAACAUCAUGGAUGUUCCUUGUGAUUGGGAAAGGAAUGAUCCACGGCAGUGAGUUUCAUUGGGGAUCCUACUCCUAUGAAAUUUGGCAUACUGCUCAGGUCAGGUUCAGAAGGUGAAUUCUUAAGGUAACUUUCACAGCAUUGCCAGAAGAAUUAGCUUUUGCUAAGUAGAUACGACAGUCUUCAUUCUGUUUUUUUCUUAGGCAGGUGGAACGUGAUCUCUCUGUCUGCUGCUCAUAGUUCCCUUGUGAGACUGGGGGGGAUAAUAGCAGGUCCAGGUGGGCAGAGUUCUGAUUUCAGUGGUAGACUCCUAUUGAGGCUGGGUGUUAGAGGGUGGAGGGCUUGGGACUUGAGUUCUUUAUUCAGUUCUUGUAACUUAACUCUUGAGUAGAUCAGUUAAUCUUAGCUGUUUGCUGUUUUGGUGGGGGCGGGGGUCGGUGUUGCAAAAUGAUAGUGUUAAAUGCCUUGCCUAACUUUGUAAGUUAUCUAAGACUUAUCAACACUAUUUGAAUUUUUCAGAGAAAAAAAACCCAGAAGGUGUUAUCUCAGAGUUGUAAUUAACCUGUUGCCUAUUGCAUAAACUUCGUGGUACAUUAACAGUACCAGUAGUUGGUGAUUCCCAUGUCGUCUUCCAUUGAUUUUUCUAAUAAUAUGAAUUUUCAUUCAAUGUUUUUGCCAUGUUUCUUCUGAAAGAAUCACCCUGUGACCUGGGAGUUGAGGCGAAAACUUUUGCUUUUACUUGUUAUUUACUUUUUGAGUGGAUCUGUUUAAAUAAAAGGUAUAACUAAUGGCUUAAUGUAAAGAAAUUAAUUGAUUUGCCUGGAUUUAAUGAAUAAAUAACUUUAGACAGAGAAAUAAUGUUUGUCUUUUUUGUCUUUUCUACAUAAUCAUGUAUGUUACUGAAUGUCUGACCCUGGUAAUACUGUAAUUAACAUAGAGCUUAUGAAUCAUAUCAUGUAUUUAAAAUUAAAUUAUGACUUCAUUUUCUUGACUUUGAUUAAUCUCUCAGCGCCAUUUAUUUGAGCAUUAAGAUUCACUUAAACUGUGGUUCUUUUGUUUUAUUUUUAAUAAUCUUUUUUUGCCUUUUUAAUGGUUGAAUCAUAACUUUAAAUAUAUUAGUAUUAUUGACUUUUAAAAAAGAAAUUAGGAAAUUGUUUAUCUCCUUAACAUAAGAUUUUUAGUGUGAUAGCUAAACGCAAAUAAUUGGCUCCUUGGGUUGGAACCAGAAAAUUUCCCAACUUCAUUCCCUUAUCAUUCUGCCACUAGUAAGUAAAUUUUGAGCAGUGGAAAGACUUCCAAAGUGGGCUAAUAUCAGUGAGGUAGGACAUGCGGUGAAGGUUACUGGGGGGUAAUAGUGGCCGAGGGGAGUGGUGAAGUGGCAUCUUACCCGGAGGAGGAAAAGUAUUUUGUUCUAAAGUUUGGAAGAGGCAGGAAAGGGUAGGAAAUGUUUUUUCUGACGGGCUUGUGCCACAAAGUUUGAGAACCAGGUCAGUAGAACCUGCAGCUCCUGCUAGUGCUUCAGUUGAAUAGUUACAGAUAGAUACCUCUUGACUCUGAAAACAUCUGUCCCAUGCCACACUGCUGACAUCUUUCCUAACACCCCACUUUACCUGGCCUCCUCAGUGGUAACUUACUUAGUCCUUGAAUCCUUGCUUCCCAUUUUAAUAGCAAGGUAACUGCUGACCCUUUCUUGAACUGUGGCUUUUUCCUGUUUUCUGGGCAUUGAAUAUAUUCAUAUAGGACUAACAUGAAUAUUUGAGUUCAGUUUGUUAGACUAUGAUUUUUGCGUAGUUUAUUCUUAUUUUUUGUUAGUAUUCUUAUACUAACAAUUAUACAUAGUUUUUUUUUUUUUUGAGACAGAGUCUUGCUCUGUCUCCCAGGCUGGAGAGCAGUGGCGUGAUCUCAGCUCACUGCAAGCGCUGCCUCCCAGGUUCACGCCAUUCUCCUGCCUCAGCCUCCCGAGUAAUUGGGACUACGGGUGCCCGCCACCGCGCCUGGUUAAUUUUUUUUUUUGUAUUUUUAGUAGAGACGGGGUUUCACCUUGUUAGCCAGGAUGGUCUCGAUCUCCUGACCUCAUGAUCCUCCCACCUCAGCCUCCCAAAGUGCGGGGAUUACAGGCGUGAGCCACCGUGCCUGGCCAGUAUACAUAGUAUUCUUAAUAGUUUAUUUAAUCUGUCCUUUCUGCUGAAUAUGUUGUUAUCUAUCAUGUUGAAACACAAGCUGAGUUUUUGAGGAUUUCUUAUGUUUUAAUAUAUACAGCUUUUAGAGAUUUUCAUUCUUUCUUAGAGGUCUGUACUAUUUUGCUUCUUCAGGAGCUCAGUUGGAUUAAUAUUAUUUCCAAUUUGUAGAAUUUUAGGUAAUCAGAAAUGCAUGAAUCUCCUUGGCUUUGACACUGAGUGAUUGUAUAACUUGAACAGUUUAUCAACUGGAUAAUACAGUUAAUUUAAUGAGUAUGUACUAUGUUCACAAGACUAGGAAUUGUAAAGAAGUGGGGAAAACUCUGAUUUCUAGCUUAAGUGAUACCUAAAGAAGCAGAGUGGGGGGGUGUACACACCCAUAUAUAUCUACAUACAUAAAUAUAUAUAUAUACACACACAUACACAUAUAUCUACAUACAUAAACAUAUAUAUAUACACACAUAGUAAAAUACUAAAUUCCAAGCCUAGAUCAGUCUUAAAAUGGAAACAUAGGACAAUAUGACACGAAUUUGUAUAAUAAUGCUAAGGAGAUGCCAUUUAAAGUAUAAAGUAUACUUAAAUGAGUUUUAUAGCUUUAUGUCACAUCUCUGAUAAUUUGAUAUAUUGUACCUGUCUUAGUUUUAGAUGCAAAUUUCAAAUUUUGCUGGAUAGCUCUACAGAAAUAUGUAUUGUCCUUACAAAUUCAAAAUACCCAAAACCUAACAAUUGUUUUAUUUAUGGCAGAAUCAUACUGAGAGGAUGAAUUGCUGAUGAUUGUAAAUGUUUUGGACUUUUCAAUCUGAAUUUAAAAAUGAAACGAGCUGACUACACAGACUUAGUCUUCUCCACUCCGUGUUCCUGCAGCUAGAGACAUGACCUAACACCCUGAUGACCACUCUCAGGGACCUUGAGUGACUGGCCGGUGCACCAUGGAACUUAAAGUAUGGGUGGAUGGAGUUCAGAGGAUUGUUUGUGGAGUCACUGAAGUCACAACUUGCCAGGAGGUUGUCAUAGCCUUAGCUCAAGCAAUAGGUCGAACUGGAAGGUACACCCUUAUAGAGAAAUGGAGAGAUACUGAAAGACACUUAGCACCUCAUGAAAAUCCUAUCAUAUCCUUAAACAAAUGGGGGCAGUAUGCUAGUGAUGUGCAGCUCAUUCUACGACGAACUGGGCCGUCUCUCAGUGAGCGACCCACUUCAGACAGUGUGGCUCGAAUUCCUGAAAGAACUUUAUACAGGCAGAGUCUGCCCCCCUUAGCUAAACUGAGGCCUCAGAUUGACAAAUCAAUCAAAAGGAGGGAACCGAAAAGGAAAUCACUGACAUUUACAGGAGGUGCCAAAGGAUUAAUGGACAUUUUUGGAAAAGGUAAAGAAACUGAGUUUAAGCAAAAGGUGCUGAAUAACUGCAAAACAACAGCAGAUGAGUUGAAGAAGCUAAUCCGUCUGCAGACAGAGAAGCUUCAAUCCAUUGAGAAACAGCUGGAAUCUAAUGAAAUAGAAAUAAGAUUUUGGGAGCAAAAGUAUAAUUCCAACCUUGAAGAGGAAAUUGUCCGUCUAGAGCAAAAGAUCAAAAGAAACGAUGUAGAAAUUGAGGAGGAAGAAUUCUGGGAAAAUGAAUUACAGAUUGAACAGGAAAAUGAAAAACAGCUGAAGGAUCAACUUCAAGAAAUAAGACAGAAAAUAACAGAAUGUGAAAACAAAUUAAAGGACUAUUUGGCACAGAUCCGGACUAUGGAAAGUGGUCUUGAAGCAGAAAAAUUGCAACGGGAAGUUCAAGAGGCACAGGUCAAUGAGGAAGAGGUUAAAGGAAAGAUCGGUAAGGUCAAAGGGGAGAUUGACAUUCAAGGCCAGCAGAGUCUGAGGUUGGAAAAUGGCAUCAAAGCUGUGGAAAGAUCUCUUGGACAAGCCACCAAACGCUUACAGGACAAAGAACAGGAACUGGAGCAGUUGACUAAGGAGUUGCGGCAAGUCAAUCUCCAGCAGUUCAUCCAGCAGACAGGGACAAAAGUUACCGUUUUGCCAGCGGAGCCCAUUGAAAUAGAGGCCUCACAUGCAGACAUUGAAAGGGAGGCACCAUUCCAGUCUGGGUCCCUGAAGCGACCUGGUUCAUCUCGGCAGCUCCCCAGUAAUCUCCGCAUUCUGCAGAAUCCUAUCUCAUCUGGUUUUAAUCCUGAAGGCAUAUAUGUAUGACAUUAUCUGUCUUUAGGGAGGAGACCCAACAGAGGUACCAAGGACAGUAAACUUCCUUUUUGAUUUGUGCCAAUGAUGAACAGAGGAUCUAUUCCACAAGACGCUGUAUGUUUUUUCUCUCCUAAAUUGCAUACCACUUGGAGCCAUACCCUGUGCACUGAUGCUAAAGAACAAAGAAACUGUGUUUUCACACAUCAACAGUGUUGAUAUUUUUGUCCAGCAGCUAUAAUGCAAAGCCUUCGUUUUUAUUUGUAGCAUUUUGAGAGCUUUAGGAAAGUAUUAUAUAGUGUGUAUACAUAAAUAAGCCGUGACUUAAGUAAGAGUGAAGAGAAAUUUGUGACUGGCUUAGUUUAAUUUAUUUCAUGUAAUCAAUGUGUGAAUGUUGAUGUUUUAAUAUUUUUAUUGACUUAUCCUGUGACUGACUUACGUUACAUAUUGUGUGAUUAUGACCGUGUGCAUGUUGCCAGACUCCAUCCAUGCAUUGCUGAUUUACACUACACAAGUGUCCUAGGGUGCUCCACCAUCGAAGCUAACUCCACAGGAAGCCACUUGCAUUUGUUUUGUGAAACUGUCCUAGCCAUUGCUUAAUUAGGUGAAAUAAUUCAGGGUUUUUUAAAUCUGGAAUUUAGUCGUUCCUUUACAAUAUUUCCAAAUAUACGUGUGGCCACAGAGCAUAACAGAUAUUUUUCAUAAGCUAAAUUGUAUGUAUAAAACAUUUGCAGUGUUUCAGACACUGUUGAACAAAAAUGUAAUUGGUAAGUAUGUAUCCAAACAGGCAUGGGGUUUCCUGAUACAUUAUGUGUUUUGUUUCUGCCCUGUCUUAUCAUUUACACUCAUGGAUCUUCAGAAUUAAUCUAACAUGGAAGUUAUAGAUACCUGAAAGCUGGGUUGGUCUACUUCAGGAACAUUGCUUUAAGUGAUGUAUUUUAAAAUAACCCGCUUCAUAUGUAUGAUCUGUUGGUGUACACACCAUGGGUAAGGUAUUGCUUGCACAUAAUUUGCUCUGCAUAUUAUGGACCAUUGUGGUUUCUUCCAGUCACUUAGAUGGAAAGGAGGUUAAACCUAGGUACUUUUUAGCAAGGAUAUAAAGUCAAAUUCAGCAUAUGUUUUUAUUUUUAGGCUUGACUUUUACAAGACAUUAAUCUCCAUUUGUACAUAUGUUAUUUUAUUUGUAAAACCAAAUAUGACUCAACACCUUUUUGAUGAGUAGUGACUUAACUAAGAUUUACAAGUAAUAUUUAGACAGAUUCAGUCAGACACCACUUAGCCAUUUUUACAUUCCCUCUGGUUAGAUUUGGUACAGUAUAAUUAAGACUUUAAUCUGAAAUUUAAAGUAGUUUUAAUUCUGAAGAAGUUACAUCCUCUGUAUUAUUUACAUGCAACAAAAUAAAAGUGGAUUAAUAUAGUAAUGCCAUGGUAACAAUAGAGCUAUGUCUUAUGCAUGAAGGCAACUUUGGAUGUUUUAACACAUUUGACUGACUUUGGUUUAGUGAAUGCUGACAAUGCUGCUCUACUUAGGUUUCCUAUGAAAUUUUUAAGAAUGGCUAUGAGACUGUAUAGAAGCUUCUAGAGAACUGAAAGUCAUAAUGCAGAGUUGCCUUUUCUAGUGCAGCUAAGUGGCGGACCUCAACUGAAGAUAUGAGUUUCUUUGGGUUCUUGGAGUUAUCAAAUUGAUCUUGCCAUUAUGUUACUUUGCAAAUAACUGAAGUAAAUGAUUCUUACCUAAAUAACCACAACCUGUACACAUUUGCUCACAAUUUAUAGUAGUUAUUUUCUAUCUACCUAUAUUUAAAAUUAGGAUGAUUAAAAAAUAAUUUAUAGAUUUUGUGACAGUAAUGAUUUACAUAUGCCCAAUAUAUGCCUUAUUUUUAAAUAAGUCAUUCUGUAUAAAGUCAUUUUGUUGUUGUUCAGAGAAAUCAAGAUCUUAUUCACAAAGAAAAACAUUUUAUAAAUUGAUCGCAUUUUCUUUAAGUCAAAAUGUUAAACUGGAGGCAGUAUUAAACUUUGCAAUUAGGAGUUUCAGAGAUGCCUUGGCAUACCACGAAAAACACUGUCAAUAUCCAACUCAUUAUAAAUUGUUAUCAGAAUUAACCUAAUAACUUUAAGUAAGGACAAGCAGCAUCCUAGCAACUUGUAGUAGUCUUGGGUUCCCAGCAGAGUAUCACAGUUAACCUCUCUGACAACUUCAUCAGAAUUUCCAAGCUGCCAAAUAAUCUUCAUAGACCUAAUUACAGAUUUAAAAAAAUUUCCUAGGCGACGAAAGUAUAGAAAUGUGAAUAUGUUGAAUACAUUGAGAAGCUGUACUUUUUAAUUAGUUAUAUUACUUCUGGAAGCACAUAUCUAAGGAAUAUUUUCUAAGACUCAGAGGGAAAAAAACUCGUUUUCAUAGGAUCAUCUGAAGAUACUUUAGUAUAUUUGUGAUCAUUUUUAUCUAUUGCAAAUACAAAUGAAUUAGAUAAGUGCCACAUCCUGGAUACAUUUCGGAGGGGUAGUGGGCAAUGGUAUACAAAAAUACCAAAUAUAAAAUUUUCAUCUGGGGGAAUGUUCAGGUUCUAAAUACUAAAUUAGAUUUCAAUGUUUUGUGUUUUUUUUAAAAAAAUCAUAUUGCAACUUGUUUUAUUGUGAUUUUCUACAAGUAUUAAAUACAUUUAAAGAUCUUUUUAUCUUACCAAGAAAUAAUUUGGAAUAGCAUUGGUAUAUUUGACCUUUUGAGUGUCUGUCAUCCUCAGAGAAUGGCCCAUAGUGUGUUGCCUGUGGACAUAGUGUCCAUAGUCCCUUUCUUGUCCUUCUGAGAUAUUUUGGUUUGAUAACAUUUUGUUUUUUGUCUUGAUGCACAGGGACUUUUUUAUAAUAUGAGACUUCAGUUGGUAUUAAUAGGAGUUACCUAUUUAAUUCUCCCAGUCAUCAAUGAGGUAAUCAUCAAUUCCUAUAGUUCAAAUUAGUCAUAAACAAGAGCUACAGCAAGACUGAUAGAGUAAAAACUAUAUAAAUACAGUAAAAAAAAAAUAGAAUUUAUGGUGUGAAAUAUGAAGUAUAGCAAUAUAUAACAAGAACAUGUAAGCACUUGCUUCCACAGCAUAAAUGUAAUUUACAUCUGCAUUAAAGGAUAAUUUUCUCUGUGAAUAAGAGCAAAAUGGUCUUCAGAGAAACAGACUGUUCAUUUGAAGCCAUUUCUGUAAACAUCUUCCAAGAUAGAACUGUAAUGGAUUGAGGAAAUAACACAGAAAAGACAAAAACUUUUGAUUUCAGGCAUGCAAAGUGCUUGGGCAGAUGGACAGUUCCCAUUGUGCAUUGCCUUUGAUAAAUUUGGCCUUAAUUUAUAUAACGAUGCUGUGUUCACAUCCCUCUCCUACCUAAAGUUGUCUUUAUUGGUUUAUAUUGUGUUAAAAUUAGCUUAUAAUUAUUACUUUUGUAUUGUGUUCAGUUUUUUAAGUUGCAUGUUUAUACUAUUUGCUACAGUAUUUUUAAGUUUGGGGUGAAGGCCAUCAGCUGUAUCAAAAAGACAAAACAAUCACUAUUUAUUCAGUAUUGCUGCUUUACAUCUCCAGAAUAAGCUUUCGAUGCCAGGACAGUGACUGCCUGAAAGCUGCAGGAGCUCUUUUCAAUGCAUUUUAUAUAUUUUUAGAAACCAAAUAAAUGCAGAAAACUAUUUCGUAUACUAAUUAUAUUAAACCAGCAGAAAUAUAAAGGCAAUAAAGUAUAUACAUAUAUAUGGGGGGAGGGGAAAGAUUAAAAAAUAGAUUUACAGCCAGACAUGGUGAUAGCCCUAAAUGUAUUUCUCAAUAUGUUUUUCUUUAUUGACCCUAGGAGGAUUUGAGUUGCUGCAGCUUUAAACAGAAAAUUGCCAUGUUCACUAAUUGUGAGCACAUAAAUAUGCUUUUAGUACUGCUUUGCUUAUGUACAAAUAAAUCUGUAAUAUGUAUUAUAUGUAAUUAUCCUUUUCUUUGACUUUCAUUUUAAAUGUAUAUUUUCUGAUCAUUAUGAGCUGUAAAACAAAGAAUCAAUAUUGGAUAUUCUCCCAAAUAAUAAAUUUUCAGGAUUCAUUGGGGCA